CAAAGCGGUUGGCAGCAGCGGCGCUUGGAGGAAAGGAAGCCGGUUGGAGGGCGCAGCGCACCCCUGCUGCGCGGAGGAGGGGGCUGAGCUGAACUCAGCAGAAGUUACAUGCACAAGGCAAAAAUUCUGACGUUCUCAAGAGACCAGCUCUGCCCCCGUGGCUCAACUGACCCUACCAUGUGGACGCUGCUCCUCCAGGUGGGAACUGGAGUUUUGAAAUAAAAUGGAUGAUUUGACGUUACUUGAUCUUCUGGAGUGCCCUGUGUGCUUUGAGAAGCUCGAUGUCACAGCCAAAGUCCUCCCUUGCCAGCACACCUUCUGCAAACCAUGUCUACAGAGGGUUUUCAAGGCCCACAAAGAGCUGCGGUGCCCCGAAUGCAGGACGCCUGUGUUUUCCAACAUUGAGGCGCUGCCGGCCAACCUGCUGCUCGUGCGCCUUCUGGAUGGAGUGCGCUCAGGGCAGAGCUCCGGGAGAGGGGGCUCCUUCCGCAGGCCUGGCACGAUGACCUUGCAGGAUGGCAGGAAAAGCAGGACCAACCCCAGACGUCUGCAGGCCAGUCCUUUCCGGCUAGUGCCUAAUGUCAGAAUCCACAUGGAUGGGGUGCCUCGAGCAAAGGCCUUAUGCAACUACAGAGGGCAGAAUCCCGGUGACCUAAGGUUUAAUAAGGGAGAUAUCAUCCUUCUCCGGAGACAGCUUGAUGAGAAUUGGUACCAGGGGGAAAUCAAUGGCAUCAGCGGGAACUUCCCAGCCAGCUCCGUGGAAGUCAUCAAGCAGCUGCCCCAGCCGCCCCCGCUCUGCAGGGCCCUCUACAACUUCGACCUACGAGGCAAGGACAAGAGUGAGAACCAGGAUUGCCUGACCUUCCUCAAGGACGAUAUCAUCACUGUGAUCAGCCGAGUGGAUGAGAACUGGGCAGAAGGCAAGUUAGGAGAUAAAGUAGGCAUCUUCCCUAUCUUGUUUGUAGAGCCAAACCUCACCGCAAGACACCUUUUAGAGAAGAACAAAGGUCGCCAGUCAUCCCGCACAAAAAACCUGUCCCUGGUGUCCUCGUCCUCCAGAGGCAACACGUCUACCCUCCGUAGGGGCCCAGGGUCCAGGAGGAAGGUGCCUGGGCAGUUUUCCAUCACAACAGCCUUGAACACUCUCAACCGGAUGGUCCAUUCUCCUUCAGGGCGCCAUAUGGUAGAGAUCAGCACCCCAGUGCUCAUCAGCUCCAGCAACCCCUCUGUGAUCACCCAGCCCAUGGAGAAAGCAGACGUUCCUUCCAGCUGUGUGGGACAGGUCAGCACUUAUCACCCCGCACCUGUCUCUCCAGGACAUUCCACAGCCGUGGUCAGUCUGCCUGGCUCCCAGCAACACCUCUCAGCGAACAUGUUUGUAGCCCUGCACUCCUACUCAGCCCAUGGACCCGAUGAGCUGGACCUGCAAAAGGGAGAAGGCGUCAGGGUCCUGGGGAAGUGCCAGGACGGCUGGCUCAGGGGCGUCUCCUUGGUCACCGGGCGAGUCGGCAUCUUCCCAAACAAUUACGUCAUCCCCAUUUUCAGAAAGACCUCUAGUUUUCCAGACUCCCGGAGCCCUGGUCUCUACACCACAUGGACGUUAUCCACCUCCUCUGUGUCCUCCCAAGGCAGCAUUUCAGAAGGUGAUCCACGGCAAAGCCGUCCCUUCAAAUCCGUCUUUGUGCCCACUGCCAUAGUCAACCCCGUGAGAAGCACAGCCGGCCCUGGGACUUUAGGACAAGGGUCUCUUCGGAAAGGGCGGAGCAGCAUGAGAAAGAGUAAGUGGUGGCAGAGAGAUGGAUCCCUGCAGAGACCCCUCCAGUCCGGGAUCCCCACUCUCGUGGUAGGCUCCCUCAGACGCAGCCCCACCAUGGUCCUUCGGCCUCAGCAGUUCCAAUUCUACCAGCCACAGGGGAUCCCCUCCUCCCCCUCAGCCGUGGUGGUGGAGAUGGGGUCCAAGCCUGCCCUCACGGGGGAGCCCGCCCUCACGUGCAUCAGCAGGGGCAGUGAGGCCUGGAUCCACUCCGCGGCCAGCUCCCUCAUUAUGGAAGACAAAGAAAUCCCCAUCAAGAGUGAGCCUCUGCCAAAACCGCCCGCAUCUGCCCCACCAUCCAUCCUGGUGAAACCAGAAAACUCAAGAAAUGGCAUCGAAAAGCAAGUCAAAACCGUGAGAUUUCAGAAUUACAGCCCUCCUCCCACCAAACAUUACACCUCCCAUCCCACCUCCGGAAAGCCUGAACAGCCAGCCACCCUCAAGGCGUCCCAGCCUGAAGCAGCGUCCUUGGGCCCAGAGAUGACCGUCCUAUUUGCCCACCGAAGUGGCUGCCACUCCGGACAGCAGACAGACCUCCGGAGAAAGUCAGCUCUUGGCAAGGCCACAACCCUGGUGUCCACUGCCUCAGGCACGCAGACCGUGUUUCCCAGCAAAUGAACCUACGGGUGGCUUUUCCUAGACCCCAAAGAGAGCCUGCCUUGGUCAUCUUCCCAGGAGGAAUUCAUGACAACUGGGAUGCAGAAGAGAGCAAAUGAUCUGCUGGGAUGGAAACUGCUCAAUGGAGAGUUUGUGGACUGCAUGAUAUUCCUUGAACAUCAGGGAUGGUACAGGGAUACCAAUAGUCUGGCCUCCAAGACAGGAGAGUAAUAGGAGGAAGAGCAAAUCUGUCUUCACCUGCAGUAUUAAUGGGUGGUGGGCCAGAAUGGAGGAAAGCAAGUGAGUCAUGUGCUGCUACAGGUUACACCAAACUCCCAUCCCUCUGUUACUCACUGCUGUUGUCAAAGCCAAACUUUAUCUUGCUAAUUUCUCACAGCUUGGCACCUAACAAAUGACAAGGCAGGACAUCCAAUGCCUUCGAGCUCUGUGGUCUGGCCUGUCUCUCCAGAUCAGAUUUAGAGUGAGGUAGCAGAUGACAUAAUAUUCUCUUUGGUGUUCAAUCCGAAGAGGCCAAUGCUUCAGCACAAUGUCCCCUAGCCAUCACCCCCAGCCCGACUCCCCACCAAGCAUCCUGCAUCCCUCUGCCACAUCUUCAUUCUUUUCCAUUCUGUCUUUUCCCCGAUACCUUCUGACCCCAGGGAUUUCUAAUAGAGCAUAAUGAUCAAGAAAAUAAAGACCUGGUACAUAAAGAGUCUCAGAAAAAAAAUCCAUGAUGUUAUAUGAAAGAUACCAAACUGCAAUGCUUACAAAGAGGCUAUUUCAAGUAGAAAGAUAUAAAUAUCACUUAUAACCAUGCAUCCUUUAUGUUCAUAAAUAAGUCAUCAUAAAGAACAAGCCAUUAGAAGACAUUCUAAUCCUUGUUUUUAAAAAAAAGACUAUAAUCUAAGAUACAAUUCUAAAAUUACUGUGCUAACCUGCAAGAGACAUUGCUCACAUAAAUGAAAUUCAUAUAUACCGUGAUGUUAUUUGAACCAUAUAUUUUCAUCUUCUCCUCCUCUCUUAAGACAUCAAUAAGAAUUUGAUUUUUAAAGGCACAUGCUGCUCUGAUUAUCAAAGACAAUAACACAAAUGCAGCAUCACUGGGAUAUGUCGGUUGUUUUAAAGUUCAGAUCCUAAUUUUACUGAGGAAGCAUCCUCAGUUUUUCAUCCAGCCCUGCUUGUAAACAGGAUCCAGCAUCAGCCAGACCAUGAGCAGAGUAAGGAUUGCAUCUGGAGGUUACAGAAAUGUUUUCUUCUAUGUGAAGCUAUCACAUGCAGGGGUUAAACAGGCAGCCAUCUUUUAAUGCGAUGAAUAAUUUGGACUUCUUAGCCACACCCUUGUCUCGGUUAACCACAGGAGGAGGUGACAAUACACCACAAGAAGCCCCAGAGUUCUGGCUUUAUCUGCCAAGUGGUAGGUGAGAAGGGAAGAGGUGGGAUUGAGCACACUGGCUAUUUAUACCUUGUCUUCAAAGCCCUCUUAGUCACAUUUCCAUCUUCAUGCAUUGGCUUCUGCCUUACAAUUGAGCAAUAGGAAACCACCACUCCUAAUUUUUGCACGUGCUGCUUUUUAAGUCUCUGGGAACUUUCCAUGAGGUAUAGUGGAGGGUUUCAUAAGGAUUUAGCUCUUCCUUCGAACCUGCUUGGCCGAUAAACCAGAUAUUUUUUUAAAACACAGCAUACAGAUUCCAAAUGAUCAAGGAUCAAAAAGUGUUGGGGAUGUCAGGAAGGAUGCAAGGAUGGGCUUGAAUGAUCACAAUGAGUCAACCCAGAAAUGUGCAGUAGAAUAGUUUGCUAAUGGUGACAUCUGAGUUGCAUCUCCCGGAAAUAUUGUUUCUUAUUAUUACACUUUGGGUCGGGGGAAGGGGUGUUAAGGGUAAAAAGAGGAAGGAGCAAAUAGAUAAAGAGAAAAAUUCAUGCCUCCAGGAAACAUAAGCAGAAAAACUAUAGACUUGUGUCUCUGCUUAUUUUUUUAAGUACAGUGUUUUUAAUAGACCAAAGAGAAUCUCUAUGAGUUAAUAUGUAUGUGAAUAAUGUUUAUAAAAGGGGUAUAAUGUGUUAGUCAUUAUGGAAUAUUGUAUAAAUAAACCUUCCAUAUAUAAAACAUAUAAAAAAUGAUUGCUUAGGGCAGUGGACACUUAAGGACUUCCAAACCUUUCAUAUCUUCAUCCCAAAAAAUAGAGCGUUCCAGGGCUGGCAACUUAUUUCCUUAGUAUAUUCCACUGUAAAGCCAAGAGGUGUGGGGGCUUGUUUUCUGGUUUUGUAAUUUGUAAUAAUCCGUAUGGAUUACUGUAAAAUGUCUGUUGCAUGUGUGUUGGUGUUGGUGUUGGUGUUGUUUACCCACAUGGAGUCAUCAGAGAUUUGUUCCACACUUUGUAUCCUGGAAAACCAAAAGGAAUUUUCUUUUCUUCGAGACAGAGUCUCGCUCUGUCGCCCAGGCUGGAGUGCAGUGGUGCCAUCUUGGCUCACUGCAACCUCCGCCUCCCGAAUUCAAGUGAUUCUCCUGCCUCAGCCUCCCGAGUAGCUGGGACUACAGGUGCGUGCCACCUUGCCCUGCUAAUUUUUUGUAUUUUUAGUAGAGACGGGGUCUCACCGUGUUAGCCAGGAUUGUCUCGAUCUCCUGACCUUGUGAUCUGCCCGCCUCGGCCUCCCAAAGUGCUGGGAUUACAGACGUGAGCCACCAUGCCCGGCCUGGAAUUUUCUAGUAAGAAGAAAAACAUACAGAAUAUGUCUUCACUGUUGGGUAACUCUCAAAUUUGUAGCAAUCCAGAUUUUUUGUAAAACUGUGCUAAUGGGAUAUUUAAUGUCAGAGUUAUUGUCUCUCACUUCAAUAUCUAGUACUGGAUAAUGUUUCUCCUGGGAGCACGUAUUUUUUUUUCAAGUCCUCUUUUCCUGGACUUAACAUGUUCUUCUAGAAGACACCAGAAGUCAUGACCCUAAGCCCCCUCCCUUCAGGACCACUUUCUACCAUCGGUUUUCAAAAAACUAUCCACAUGUUAAUUCUGUUUUAUGUUCUGUGAUUCUGUGGUAGACUCAGUGCUUUCAGAGUCCAGAGCUUGACUUGGGUUAGUGGCCUUAAUGAAGUGCUAAAUUUGCUCUUUACCGCGAGACUGAUCAGAAGAAGCAAAAGGGGAAAGGGGGCUAGAGGUCCACUCGCACCUUUUACAUCAGACAAGAGGAGGACUGUGCCAGAAAUCUGUGCAUGAAACACCAUCUGCUCUUCAUGCAGGGAGGGGUCAACCGUGUGAACGUGCAGAGAUUACUCGAGCCUUCUUUGCCAAAAAUAUGCAUUCUUCCCAGCUGUAAGCGUGUGAAGCCAAAUAUGUCUUUUAGCAUGAAACAAUAAAAACAUGUUUAUUUUCACUUAA